GAUGAAUUCAGUGGCAGUGAAUUGAGACCGGAGGGAAUCUGGCCCCUAGAGGCUGGUACUUGGGCCCGAAACCCCCAUCUCCGGCGGAGAGACCGUCCGAGGUAAUUGUCUGCCACGAGUGCACAUUCUGAAAACAGGAGAUUUUAGUUCCUAAAAAUGGGAAGAACCUACAUUGUAGAAGAGACUGUUGGCCAGUAUCUUUCAAACAUAAAUCUCCAAGGAAAGGCUUUUGUCUCUGGCCUUUUAAUAGGACAGUGUUCGUCACAAAAGGAUUAUGUGAUUCUUGCCACUAGAACGCCACCCAAAGAGGAGCAAAGUGAGAACCUCAAACAUCCCAAAGCUAAGUUGGAUAACUUGGAUGAAGAAUGGGCCACAGAACAUGCCUGCCAGGUAUCCAGAAUGCUACCAGGGGGACUUUUAGUUCUUGGAGUAUUUAUUAUUACUACUUUAGAACUGGCAAAUGAUUUUCAAAAUGCCCUGCGUAGACUAAUGUUUGCUGUGGAAAAGUCUAUAAAUAGAAAGAGAUUGUGGAAUUUCACAGAGGAGGAAGUCUCAGAACGAGUGACACUUCACAUUUGUGCUUCUACAAAAAAAAUAUUUUGUCGAACUUAUGAUAUCCAUGAUCCAAAGAGUUCAGCAAGACCAGCAGAUUGGAAGUAUCAAAGUGGAUUAUCAUCCUCAUGGCUUUCUUUAGAGUGUACAGUUCACAUUAAUAUUCACAUCCCACUUUCUGCUACUUCUGUCAGCUAUACUCUGGAGAAAAAUACAAAGAAUGGACUUACACGCUGGGCCAAGGAAAUAGAAAAUGGUGUUUAUUUGAUUAAUGGACAAGUUAAAGAUGAAGAUUGUGACCUAUUAGAAGGACAGAAAAAAUCUUCUAGAGGAAAUACUCAAGCAACUAGUCAUUCUUUUGAUGUCAGAGUGCUAACGCAGUUGCUCCUGAAUUCAGACCACAGAUCCACAGCCACAGUCCAGAUAUGUAGCGGUUCUGUAAACCUUAAGGGUGCUGUGAAAUGCAGAGCUUAUAUCCACAGCAGUAAACCCAAAGUUAAAGAUGCUGUGCAGGCAGUAAAGAGGGAUAUAUUGAACACAGUUGCUGAUCGUUGUGAAAUGCUAUUUGAGGAUCUGCUUUUGAAUGAAAUUCCAGAAAAAAAAGAUUCUGAAAAAGAGUUCCACGUCCUCCCUUAUCGAGUCUUUGUUCCCCUUCCUGGAUCCACUGUAAUGUUGUGUGAUUAUAAAUUUGACGAUGAGUCAGCUGAAGAAAUCAGGGACCAUUUUAUGGAGAUGUUGGAUCACACAAUUCAAAUAGAAGAUUUGGAAAUUGCAGAGGAAACAAACACAGCUUGUAUGAGUUCUUCUAUGAAUAGUCAAGCUUCAUUGGACAACACAGAUGAUGAACAACCAAAACAACCAAUUAAAACUACAAUGUUAUUGAAAAUUCAGCAAAACAUAGGUGUGAUUGCAGCAUUUACAGUUGCAGUCCUUGCUGCGGGUAUCUCCUUUCAUUACUUCAGUGAUUAGGGAAACCUUAAAGUCUCAUCUCAAUAUGACAUCAAGUUCAAGCUCAAGACCCAGAAUCUCAUGAUCUAAACCAGUUUCAGUAACAUAUGAGGCACCUUUACUACAGUUUCCCUCAAUCCGAAGAUGUGUGAAACUAAAGACAAGUUUUCUUUCCCAUAUUCACCCAGCCUACGAUGGUGAGUCAGGCAAUAUACACUCUUGUUUAAAAAAGAGGAAAAAUGAGAGGUACAUAGCAGUGAAUGGUUCAUAGCAAUUCUGAACUCCAAUUGGGCACGUCUAAUUCCUUAUGAUUCUGGGAGCACAGAAUGUAUGUCAAUUAGGGCCUAAUUCUACCUGAGAGUGGUUCUCAACUCUUGGCUCUUCCCUGUAAGAUCUUGACUUUGCUCUGAGUCAUUCUUUUCCAUGACUUUUCCAUUAGAAAAUCCAUACUCAUCUCUUCAAGACAGGCCUGUCUCUAAUUUGAACUCAGAGGAUGUUGAGGAACAGCACCCUUAACUACCUUAGAUACUCAUUAUCGAGCAAAGUAAUCUACAAAAUGUGCUCAUAAGAUUCUUAGAAGUCUUUUUGUCUAGCUAAGAGGUCUAUGAGGCACUGGCUUAAAUAUUUCUGAAACCUUAAAGGAUAUUACAGAUGCACCGUUGAUCCUAAAUUAUCCUAAUUCUAUGGUUUACUAACAAUUCUUGAUUUGAUCUUUGCCAUAAGGUGAUUUCUUCCUUGAGAACCUCUUGCUGGCUGGAAAAGAUGUUCUACACACUUUAAAUAUUCUAUAAAUUUUGCUCCAAAACUGAACAGUUUCUUAGUUUAUUUCUCUCUUCUCCUGUUUGAUGAUAGGCAGCUAGAAGUAGUCAGGUGGCAUUUUCCAUGUUUGCCUGGAAGUCUCCUUGGAUAGAUUCACAAAUUUAUUAGGUUAUGUUUUCCCUUUAGCAAUUGCCAUGAGCUUAUUAGUUCUACCUUUCACGUUACUGCAAAUGAAAGUGUUGCCUUUCUGUUUUCUCAUUGAUCUUCUAGCCACCACUGUCUGUAUUUCCUGUUUAAUUCCAAAGUUGAGGCUACGUAAGUUUUGGGUUUGACCAAGUGGCACCCUAUUUCUAGAUACCAGUUUCUAUUGCAGUUAUCUUUUGCUCCACAACAAACAACCUCAAAACUUAGUGGCUUAAAGCAACCAUUUUGUUAACUCAUGACUCUUUGUAUAGAAGGAACUUAGCUGACUCAGUUGGGUGGCCCUGCUCCACGUGAUGCUGUGUGGGGUAUUCAAUUAUCUAAAGGCUGUGAUAUCCAAGACAGUUCAUCCACAUGGUUGACAGUUUAUCUGGUUUUCCUUCACGUGACUUUUCCAAAGAGUUUGGCUUCCCACAGCAUGGUGAUUGAAUUCCAAAAGGGAGUGUUCCAAGAUUCAGUGUUCAGAGAUGAAAGAUGUGGAAACUGUUCAUCCUCUCAAGGCCUGGUCUUCUCAGAAGUUCCAGAAUGUCACUCUUUGCAUUCUACUGGUCAAAGCAAACACAGAUCCAGUCCAGUUUCCACAGGAGAGGAAAAAGAAGCCCAUAUCUCAUUGGGGAAGUGGCAUAUGCUUGUAGAGAGAGAAAGAAUUGAUGGCAGUCAUUACUGGAGAUUUGUAACUACACAUUUUUAGUAUAUGUCAAAAAAAGAAGAUUGAAAAUAUAAUCAUACCUCAGAGAUAUUGUGGGCUGGGUCCCAGACAACCAAAACUAAGCUAAUAUCAUAAUCAAGUCACAAUUUUUUUUUGUUUUCCCAGUGCAUAUAAAAUUAUUUUUAUACUGUAGUCUAGUAAGUGCACAAUAGCAGUAUGUCUAAAUAACAAUGUAUAUACCUUAAUUUAAAAAUACUUUGCUGCUAAAAAUAAAAGUGGCAAUCCUCUGACCUUUCAGCCAUAAUCUUUUUGACCUUCAGUCAUAAUCUUCAUAACCUUCAGUCAUAAUCUUUUUGAUGGUGGAAGGUUUUUGUCUUGAUGUUGAUGGCUGUUGACUGAUUAGGGUGGUGGUUGCUGAAGGUUGGGGUGGCCAUGGCAAUUUCUUGAAAGACAAUGACAUUUGCCACAUCAAUUGACUCUUCUUUUCAUGAAAGAUUUUUCUGUAGCAGGUGAUGCCAUUUGAUAGCAUUUUACCCACAGUAAAACUUUCAGAAUUGGAGUCAGUCCCCUCAAACCCUAUGGCUUCUUUUUCAACUAAGUUUGUGUGACAUUCUGAAUCCUUUGUUGUCAUUUCAACAGUGUUCACAGCAUCUUUGCCAGGAGUAGGUUCUAUCUCCAGAAGCCACUUUAUUUGCUCAUCCUUAAGAAACAACUCCUCAUUCAUUCAAGUUUUAUCAUGAUAUCGCACCAAUUUAGUCACAUCUUUAGGCUCCACUUCUAAUUCUAGUUCUUUUGCUAAUUCUAUCACAUCUGUAAUUACUUCUUCCACUGAAGUCUUGAGCCCCCUCAGUCAUUCAUGAGGGUUGGAAUAAAAUUCUUCCAAACUCCUGUUAAUGUUGAUAUUUUCACCUGCUUCCAUGAGUCACAAAUGUUCUUAAUGACAUGUAGAAUGAUUAAGCUUUUCCAAAGUAUUUUCAAUUUAGUUUGUCCAGAUCCAUCAGAGGAAUCACUAUCUUUGGCAGCUAUCACCUUACAAAAUGUAUUUCUUAAAUAAUAAAAGUUGAAAGUCAGAACUACUUCUUGAUCCAUGGUCUGAAGAAUAGAUGUUGUAUUUGUAGGUAUGAAACAAACGUUAAUCUCUGCAUAUCUCCAUAAGAGCUCUUGGAAUAAUAUUUUGAAAGGAAUCGUUUUCUGAGCAUUAAGUUUCAACAGUGGGCUUAAAAUAUUCAGUAAAACAUGAGGAAAGUAGACGUGCUGUCAUCCAAGCUUUACUUUUCAUUGGUAGAGCAUGGACAAAGUAGAUUUUGCAUAAUCCUUAAGCGCCCUAGGAUUUUUGGAAUGGCAAAGGAGCUUUGGCUUCAACUUAAAGUCACCAGGUGCAUUGGCCCCUAAAACAAGAGUCCGUCUGUCCUUUGAAGCUUUGAAGUCAGGCAUUGACUUCUCCUCUCUAGCUAUGAAAGUAGAUGGGAUCUUCUUCCAAUAGAAGACUGUUUAAUCUACAUUGAAAAUCUAUUGUUUAGCCACCUUCAUUGGUUAUCUUACAUAGAUCUUCUGGAUAACUUGCUGCAGCUUCUACAUCAGUACUUGCUGUUUCACCUUGUACUUUUAUGUUAUUGAGAUAGCUUCUCUCCUUAAACCCCAUGAACCAACCUCUGCUAGCUUCAGACUUCUUCUGCUUCCUCACCUCUCUUAGUCUUCACAGAAUUGAAGAGAGUUAGGGCCUUGCUCUGGACUAGGCUUUGUCUUAAGGGAAUGUUGUGGCUGGUUUGAUCUAUCUAAACCACUCAGACUUUCUCCAUAUAAGCAAUAAGGCUAUUUCACUUAUUCAUAUGUUCACUGGAGUAGCACUUUUAAUUUCUUUCAAGAACUUUUCCUUUGCACUCACAACUUGGCUGUUUGUUGCAAGAGGCUUAGCUUUCAGCCCGUCUUGUCUUUCGACAUGCCUUCCUCAUUUAGCUUAAUCAUUUCUAGCUUUUGGUUUAAAGUGAGAGACAUAUACCUCUUUCUUUCACUUGGACACUUACAGGCCAUUGUAGGGUUAUCAACUGGCCUAAUAAUAAUAAUAUUGUGUUUCAGAGAAUAGGGAUAGGGAGAAAGACAGGGAAAUGACUGAUUGGUUGAGUAAUCAGAACACACACAAUUUUAUCAAUUAAGUUUGCCAUCUUAUAUGGGCAUGGUUCAUGGAACCCCAAAACAAUUAUAAUAGUGACAUCAAAGUCACUGAUUACAGAUCACUGUAACAGAUAUAAUAAGGCUGGGCAUGGUGGCUCAUUCCUAUAAUCCGAGCACUUUGGCGAGUAAAUCACUUGAGCCUGGGAGUUCAAGACCACUCUAGGCAACGUGAUGAAAUCUUGUCUCUACAAAAAGAAAAACAACAACACCAAACAAAAAUUAACUGGUUGUGGUUGGCACAUGCCUGUAGUCCCAGCUACUUGGGAGACUGAGGUGGGAAGACCACCUAAGCCUGGGAGGCCGAGGCUGCAGUGAGCCAUGAUUGUGCAACUGCAUUCCAGCCUGAGUGCACACACUGAGCCUGGGUGACACACUGAGACUCUGUCUCAAGAAAAAAAAAAGACAAUGAAAAUGAAGAAGUUUGAAAUAUUACAAGAGUUACCAAUAUGUGAUACAUAGACAGAAAAUGAGCAUAUACUGUUGGAAAAAUUACGAUAGACUUGCUUGAUGCAGGGUUGUAAAAACUUUCUACUUGUAAAAAAUGAGGUAUAUGUGAAAUGCAAUAAAGCCAACUACAAUAAAAUAAGAUAUGCAUGUUUAGGAGAAAGAACAGACAAAAGAGUUCCCUAAAGAAAUAGUUACUACAAAAAAAAAUCCACAUAUGACCCUUAAUCGCAGUCUGUCUUUUACUACAGUGCCUCUGUCUUCCUCUUUUUCACUGUGACAAUUCUGGGGACAAAUAAAAUGUCUUUUCUUUUACCUACCCCUACAAUCCUCAAUAGUCAAUAGGUUCAUGACUAUAUCACCAACAUAGCUAGGAAUAAUCAAGCCCUAUUAUAAUAUAAUGUCAUUAUGUUUGCUGACUCUUACCUAAAAGAUUUGUCUAAAUAUAAAUUAACCAAUGCAUAAUAAAUACCUGGUAAGUUGUUCUUGAUUUCUGAUUUUAACCUAAUAAAUAAUUAUGUUGGAAAUAUCAAGUCUGUUAAUGAAUAUUAAUCAAAGGUGGUCAAUGAGGUCUCAUAAAAUUUAUAACAUUUUAUUAAAAGGUAAAUUAAUAUGUUAAUAGGUAUUGAUUUGUUAGUUGUUAAGAACAAAGGAUGAAAGUAGAGUUAGAAGUUACAGUUGUUUGUUUUUGCCAUUUUGAAAGUGUUUCAGUUUCAUUAUUUCAUUGGAUUUUUAUAACAGUUUUGUAUUGUAUGUAGGGAAAAGAUUUGUUAGAUUCAAAUUGUAUUAAUAUAAUAGAAAUAGACUUUGAUUAUUAUUCAUAAGGACACAUAGAGUAGAUAUUUGGGUAAAUAACUAUUAUCUUUGUCUUAAUAAUCAGAAGUAGAUUAUUUCUUCUUUUUUCAUCUUUGUAAAAAUAUAGGUAUUUUAUUUACUUAACACCAUUAAAUGAAGCUAGAUUUUGUACUGUACUAUGGAACUUCUGAUCCCAGAAGAGCACUGUACAAAAAUCCUUAAUUAAAAAGGCUUGGUAUUUUAGAAAACUAUCCUUUAUUCAACUUGCUCAAUUUGUUGAGGAGAUUUUUUGUUUACAGAAUGGUGAAGAGGAACUUAAUGAUAGAGAUGAAGGUAGUUUAAUCAGGUCUUAGAUUCUAUUUUAGGCAAAUCCAAUUUAGUUGUAGAAACACCAGAUGCCUACCCCCAUGAUUAAAAUUCUGAAUGUCAAUAAGCUAAGAUGUUAGACUGCAAUUUCUGUGUUUAACAAAAAUAACCAACAUAAUUUUAAUAUUUUUUUCUGUGCUUUCAAGUUAGCACUAUUAAAAUAUUUUCUAGUUUUUAAUUAUAAGUAGUUAAUAAUUAUGGAGAAUUGAGUUAUAUUCCUAGAUCUGCCAAAAGAAAAAUAAUAAAACCUUGUGAAGUCAGUUAAUUCCUUUGAUCUUUAAGUGGGAACAAAUUCUAACAUUACACUAACUCUCAAUAAAUAGUGCUUUACAGUUUACAAAGUAUUUUCAUUUCUAUGUCACCCUCCCUCCCUUUUUUUUUUUUUGUUUUAAUAAUUCAGAAACAGGUUCAGGAAAGUCAUUUUCUAAGCCUAAAUAUUACUGUGCAUAUACAGAUUAAGGGGAAACAUACUGAUGAAAGGGAAUAAUUAAGCGUGUAGAAACAAGAUAGAUGACUGUACACAACUAAGAAAACAUAAACAUAAGAUUUUUGGAAUGUUGGAGAGGAUACACUUUAAAGCACAGGUGGCUCUUGGCCUUUAGAGAAGGAACACCUCUUCUAGCAUAAUAGCUCAGAGGGGGAAGAAAAUAGGUGUAAAUAUAUACGGACUUGUAGGUGUGCUGGUGAAAAGUUGAAGAUAAUCUCAUCUGAUGCUUCAGAUUUCUAUAAAAUUGUCAAGGUCAUCUUCCAAGAGUGAAGGAUGAUGAAAAUAAAGAUUUGUAAGAAGUAUUGCAAAGAAUGGAAUAUCAAGUGGCCAAAGAAAAAUCGUGGAAUUGCCAGAGAGUGGUAAAAAUCCUUCUGAGGUUAGUAAUCACAUGAUUAAGUUGUGUAUUUUUCCCCCAGCAAUCUUUGUCUUCUCGGAUUCAAGAAUAGAAAAAAAUGAAGAGCAAUAUUUGGGAGGCUUAUCUAAUAGACAGAUGAGUUGAAAUUAAAAAAGGUCAUAGAAAUUUAGUUUAAUGAUGGCCACAAAACUUAAGCAGAAAGGUAGAGUAAUUAGAAGGUCAAUAUUUGUCAGUUGCAAGGAUGGAAAAAAAGUGAUACAUACAAAUAGCAUGACCCUAAAAGAUAUGUAGUAUUUUUAUGGAAGCCAAUGAGAAGAAUAAUCUGGGGUAAGGGAUAGUGUCACUAAUGAUAUUUGAAUUCUGAAAUAAUACAAAAUCACCAUUUGCAAGCUUAAAGAGAAAGUGUACCCUCUUUGAAGAGGCAGAUUUCAGUAAUGGCAAAGAUGUGGAAGGAAUUCUUGGAUAAAAGGUUGAAAAUAGAGGGAAAUUCUGAUUUUAGAGAGCAAGGAAGUACAGACUUUCAUGGGGAUGGUGUAGUAGAGUAUUAAGGCGAAGGGCAAGCUGGGAGUGGGCAGGAAGUAGGGAGUGGGAAAAGUUGGUAGGGGGCUUAUGUUUUAGAUACUGAUUGUGAUUAAUGCAAGAUUAAGAAUCAUGGUGGGUUCAGUUUCAUAGUUUUUGAGGAUGUUAGAUUCUGGUUCUAAUAAAGAAUUUGUCUCAUUCAGCCUAAGUGAGUAAUUACCUCAGUGGGAACAAGUUUUGGUAGCUUCUCAUAUAUGGCUUGGAGGUGGGAGGGGACCUAGGUAUUGAUGCCAGCAACUAAAGACAUUAAGGCUACAGUAGGAACAUAACCUAUAGCUACAAACUGUGAGCUUUAUAUAUCCAACCUUAUAUUCCAGGUAGAAAUCCAACUUGAUCAUGUUUUAUCUUUUACAUACACUGUUGGAUUUGACUUGCUAAUAUUUUAUUUAAAUUUUUUGUUUCCAUACUUGUGGAAAUAUUAGCCUGUAAUUUUCCCUUCUCAUACUGCCCUUGUCCAGUUUUGGUACAAAGAUUAUAUGAGUUUAAUAAAAUGAGUUGAUAAUUAUUCUCCUUUUCUGUUCUCUGAAAAAGCCUGUGUAAAAUAAUGUUUCUUUUCAGAUUGAUAGAAUUAACUUAUAAAUACAUCUAGGCCCUGUGUUUUUUUGGGGGGUAAUAUUUUGUUAACUACUGUUCUGGUUUCUUUGCUGGUUACAGGGCUAUUCAGACUUUCUAUUUGUCUUAAAUCAAUUCUGGUAAAUUAUAUUUUUCUAGAAAUCUAUUUUUUUUGUUUUCAAAUUUGUUGGCAUUAAGUUGCUCAUAAUAUUUUAUAUCAUUUUUAUCUCAGCUCUAUCUAAGCAUGUGUUUUAAAAAAUUUUUUUAAUGUUGUUUAUUUAUGCUUUUCUCAUAGCCACCACACCCCCUGCAGUGAAUCUGGCAGAUUUUUUUUUUUUUUUCUUGAGACGGAGUCUCACUCUGUCACCCAGGCUAGAGUGCAAUGGUGUGGUCUCGGCUCACUGCAACCUCCACUUCCUGGGUUCAAGCAAUUCUCCUGCCUCAGCCUCCUGAGUAGCUGGGACUACAGGCGCAUGGCAACACACCAGGCUAAUUUUUGUAUUUUUAGUAGAGAUGGGGUUUCACCAUGUUGGUCAGGCUGGUCUCGAACUCCUGACCUCAAGAUCCAUCCGCCUCAGCCUCCCAAAGUGCUGGGAUUACAGGUGUGAGCUACCGCACCCGGCCAGAUAUUUAAAAAUCUUAUUAGAGAACCAAUUUUUGGCAUGUGAAUUCUAUCUAUAAAAUUUAUAUUAAUUUAUGCAUGUACUUAUUUCCUUAUGUUUGUACUUUGUGGGUUUGCUUUAUUUUCUUAACUUAGUUGGAAACUCAGGCCAUUUGUUUUAAGUCUUCUUUUGUAAUUUAUGUUUUUAAUAGUAAUAUUUUCUUGAUGUUCCAAAGUUUUGAUAUAAAAUACUCUUAUUUUUUUUUAAGUUUUAAGAAUUUCAGAUUUCCAGUAUAAUUUAUUCCUUGAACACAGAAGUUAUUUAGAUGUAUGUGUAUUUAUUAUUAAUAGCAAAUACAUAUUUGUAAUUAAUUUCUACUUAAUUGCAUUGUGGUCCUAAAGAGUAAUUUGUCUUACAGUAUACUAGUUCAUUAUUAACUUUUGAAAAUGUUCCUUGUGUGUUGGAGGUGGAAAAGUGGCUACUUUACUAAUUAUUAGUUACAAUGCUUUAUUUUUAUUAUUUUAUUAUUAUUAUUUUGAGACAGAGUCUCACUCUGUGGCGCAGACUGGAGUGCACUGGUGUGAUCUCAGCUCACUGCAACCUCUGCCACUUGGGUUCAAGCGAUUCUCUUGCCUCAGCCUUCCAAGUAGCUGGGAUUACAGGUGCCUGCCACCACACCUGGCUAAUUUUUGUAUUUUCAGUAGAGACGGGUUUCGCCAUGUUGCCAGGCUGGUCUUGAACUCCUGACCUCAGGUGAUCCACCCACCUCGGCCUCCCAAAGUGCUGGGAUUAUAGGCAUGAGCCACCGCGCCUGGCCAGUUGCAGUGUUUUUAAUAUGUCCUUUAGAUCAAACUUGUUAAUUCUGUGGUUAAUAUCUACAUAGAUACUAAUUUUUUGUUACGCGAUCUAGCAAAGGUUCAAAGAACUGCACUGAAAUUUCUGAUGGUGGAUUGCCACUUUUUUCCUGUAGUCUGUCAGUUUUUACUAUGUAUAUUCUGUGACAUUUUAUUAGCCAUAUAUAUGUUUAAAAUUUUUAGAUCAUCCUAGUGGUACUGUACCAUUUUAUAGUUAUGUAAUAAUGUAAGUAAUAUUAUGUAUAUAAGAUAUAUUUCUAUAUCUAAUAAUGCUUUUUCUCUUUAAAUGUAUUUGUCUGAUAUUAAUUGAUACUUGCUUAAAGAAUUGUAUUUGCUAGAUAUAGUUUUUCCAUCAUUUUACAUCUUGCUUUUCUGUAUCCUUAUGUUUUGAAUGUAUCUCUUUUGAAUAGCCAAUACCUGGGUUUAAAAAAUGUCUAAUUAGACAAUAUAUACCUCAUAACUGUUAAAUUGAAAUCAUUUAUGGUUUUUGUUACUAUUAUUAUGUUUGGAAUGAUUGCCUCUUUAAAUUCUUACUCUGGAACUGGAAAGAAUGGUAAAAUAACUCUGGUUUCAAAUAGAAACUCCUUGCUGCUCCUUCAGAGAAAGCCAAAUGGAGGUUUAAAAGUCCUUUCCAUUUCCCUACCAAAACAAAAGCAACAAAAAAGAAAAUUAAAAAUCCUCAUUCUCUGGAAAUGCUUGAAGAAGGGAAAAAAUAAAUUGGAGAUACAAUGAUUGGCAAAAAUGACAUCUUUAUUUAUUUUUAAUAAAAGAUAAAUGUAAUGUAGAGCCAUGGCCUUAUUCUUCUAAACUUCUGUGGGACUUACACAGUUUAUUAUGUAAGUCUCUGUAAUUCAAGUUACCCGGAAAGUUCAAUUUCAUGUGUGAUUAUUAUUGCCUAUUGAAAGUGCAUCUGAUUUGUUAUAACAGGAACCCUGUAGGGGAAAUAAUUGUAUGUUGUUAGCAAUGAAUAUAUGUAAACCUUUAAAAAUGAAUUAAUGUUUUUGAUAUAGCAUGUUUAAUUCAAGCUAGUCUGUGUUCAAUUAUUGGAAGCAGGGAGUGAACGCUCUAAGAAAUAAAAUAACCUAGGGUGAAACACCUUAUUUUAUGAAAAACUAA